GGCUUUUCUCUUUAGCGCUCAGGGCGCUGACCCACUGCUCUUCCUCUUAAGAAAGUGCUCCAUUCCUUCCGGCGCCCGGAGCUGCUGGCCCAAAGGGAUCCGGAGCGAGCUAGGGCAGACACCAUGACCACCCUUGAUGAUAAGUUGCUGGGGGAGAAACUGCAGUACUACUAUAGCAGCAGUGAGGAUGAGGACAGUGACCACGAGGACAAGGACCGAGGCAGAUGUGCCCCAGCCAGCAGUUCUGUGCCUGCAGAGGCUGAGCUGGCAGGCGAAGGCAUCUCAGUUAACACAGGCCCAAAAGGUGUGAUCAAUGACUGGCGCCGCUUCAAGCAGUUGGAGACAGAGCAGAGGGAGGAGCAGUGCCGGGAGAUGGAAAGGCUGAUCAAGAAGCUGUCAAUGACUUGCAGGUCCCAUCUGGAUGAAGAGGAGGAGCAACAGAAACAGAAAGACCUCCAGGAGAAGAUCAGUGGGAAGAUGACUCUGAAGGAGUUUGCCAUAAUGAAUGAGGACCAAGAUGAUGAAGAGUUUCUGCAGCAGUACCGGAAGCAGCGAAUGGAAGAGAUGCGGCAGCAGCUUCACAAGGGGCCCCAAUUCAAGCAGGUUUUUGAGAUCUCCAGUGGAGAAGGGUUUUUAGACAUGAUUGAUAAAGAACAGAAAAGCAUUGUCAUCAUGGUUCAUAUUUAUGAGGAUGGCAUUCCAGGGACCGAAGCCAUGAAUGGUUGCAUGAUCUGCCUUGCCGCAGAGUACCCAGCUGUCAAGUUCUGCAAGGUGAAGAGCUCAGUUAUUGGCGCCAGCAGUCAGUUCACCAGGAAUGCCCUUCCUGCCCUGCUGAUCUAUAAGGGGGGUGAAUUGAUCGGCAAUUUUGUUCGUGUUACUGACCAGCUGGGGGAUGAUUUCUUUGCUGUGGACCUUGAAGCUUUUCUCCAGGAAUUUGGAUUACUCCCAGAAAAGGAAGUCUUGGUGCUGACAUCUGUGCGUAACUCUGCCACGUGUCACAGUGAGGAUAGCGACCUGGAAAUAGAUUGAACUGAUAGUCUAGUUGCAUAGAUUUCUCAUUGUUUGGGUUGGAAUACACGUCAUUGUUUAUUUUUGUUCCUUUGUCUUCUGGCUUUUCAGCUGUUCUUUGUAGUCCCUUUUAUUAUGCAUAAAAUAAAGAAAUUCUUAGAUUAAAUCAGAAUGCUGAAUAACCUUGUAGCUAGCAAUAAGGUGACUUACAGUUGUAUAAACAGGAAGCCAGGCUUUUGAACUGUUUACUUAAGAUUCUGUGGUGUGACAUCUCUGUUAUUGUUUCCAGUCAAUAUUUACAAAGCAUCCUAAAGACAGGGUCUUGGAAAUUGUCUUCAGAUGAUCUUAGAGGUCUCUGCCAAGUCUGAGAGUAUAAUUCUGUAGGUAUUGUGUUAUUUGCAACGUAAAUAGUGCAUUUUCUUAAUCAAAUGAUUGUAAAUUAUAUUUACUUGUAAUCAGUUCCAUAGCUUUAGACGGUGGUUAGAUUUUUUUUUUCCCCACCAGGGUCUUGUUUAAAGGGGUGAGCCACCGCACCCAGUCCUGAGGGGUGGCCUCUGCUGCUGGAUUUCAUGUCUUCCUCCAGCAUGACUAAGUCUGGAACAGCAGGAAGGGUUGAUGCUUACUGACCUGGUGAUGUUAGAAGACAAGUAGUUUAUGGAUUUAAACAUUAGAGCUGGAGUGGGGCUGGAAAUCUUUGUAAAGGAAGUUCUUUCAGUAAGAUGCCCCUGCUUGUCUUUGUCUCUUUUUUGUUUAACAAGGUAACUUUUUGUUUAACAAGGUAACUUUUUGUUUAACCUAGAUUUUUUUUAAAACUUUUUUUUUUUUUCAUAUUGGAAAAGUAAUUCAUAUUCAGUAGAGGAAAACUGACCAAAACAGAAGCAAAAAUAAGAAAAUUAAAAUAAUCUCUAAUCCUACUACCUAGAAUAAAACACUAUUAAUAUUUUGGUCUGUUUCCUGCCAAGGUGUUUUCUGUGUAUACAUGGAUAUUUUGUUUGUUUUUAAACAAAACGAUGGGAUCAUUCUGAACAUACUGUUCUAUAGUAUGGUCAGCUAAUAAUAUAUCAGACCUUUUUUUAUAUUAUUAAAUAUUCUACAACUUUUUAAAAAUGUCUAUUAAUAUUCCAUCGUAUAGAUGUGAUAUAAUUUGCUUGAUGGUUGUCUCUUAAAAAGAAAGAUAGCAAAUACUUUUUUUAAAUUACAAAAGUGAUAGAUGUUCAUUGUAGAAAAUGUAAUAAACACUGUUAAGACUUAAAAGCCAUAUAAUUCCACCAACCAAAAUUAAUCCCUUUUGUCAUAUUUCUAGUCAUUUUUAUAGCCUUUUUUUCUAUGUAUUUAUAAUAAUUAUCAUUUGCGUUUUUUUCCUUUUUUUAACUUUAAAAAUGUAUAUUCUAGGGUCAGGGGAAAUGUAAUCUGGAAUUAAAUAUUAGCCUUAAAAUUCACAAUUUUGAUUUUCCUGGCUUUUCAGGAAUUGACUAACUGUAAAAGAGUCUUGAAAGUAUUUAGUCAACAAACAGAGUGCAUUUUUUUUUUUUUUGACUAAGAAAGCUCGUUGUAGUAGAAAGGGUGGAAUGUAUUGAAAAUUAUUAGAAGCAGGGAAGUAUUGUUAGUCUAGCUUAUUUCCUUUCAGUCUUUUUUCAAUAUUUUUAUAAACAUUGAGUACUUACUGAAUUUAGUUCUGUGCUCUUCCUUAUUUAGUGUUGUAUCAUAAAUACUUUGAUGUUUCAAACAUUCUAAAUAAAUAAUUUUCAGUGGCUUCAUAAUAUUUCAUCAUUUGGAUAUAUAAUAAUUUAUUUAACCAGUCUCUUUAUUUUUAUUUAUUUAUUUUGUUUGUUUUCUUUGAGAUGGAGUCUCGCUCUGUCACCCAGGCUGGAGUACAAUAGCGUGAUCUCGGCUCACUGCAACCUCCACCUCCUGGGUUCAAGCAGUUCUCCUGCCUCAGCCUCCUGAGUAGCUGGGACUACAGGCACAUGCCAUCACGCCUGGCUAAUUUUUGUAUUUUUACUAGAGAC